AAUAAUGAAGGUGGCUGCGGCGCGGCGGCAGGCUCAGCUGCGCCGGGCGGGGGCGGCGCCGGGGCCGCGCCUGUAGGACUCGGGGCCGACGCCGCGGGAUGGGGACGCGGCGCGGGGAGUGAGGCAGUGGCGGCGGCGGCGGUAAGCGGAACUUCGGCCCGAGGGGCUCGCCCGCUCCCGCCUCUGUCUUGUCGGCCUCCACCUGCAGCCCCGCGGCCCCCGCGCCCCGCGGGACCCGGACGGCGACGACGGGGGAAUGUGGCGCUGGAUCCGGCAGCAGCUGGGUUUUGACCCACCACAUCAGAGUGACACAAGAACCAUCUACGUAGCCAACAGGUUUCCUCAGAAUGGCCUUUACACACCUCAGAAAUUUAUAGAUAACAGGAUCAUUUCAUCUAAGUACACUGUGUGGAAUUUUGUUCCAAAAAAUUUAUUUGAACAGUUCAGAAGAGUGGCAAACUUUUAUUUUCUUAUUAUAUUUUUGGUUCAGCUUAUGAUUGAUACACCUACCAGUCCAGUUACCAGUGGACUUCCAUUAUUCUUUGUGAUAACAGUAACUGCCAUAAAGCAGGGAUAUGAAGAUUGGUUACGGCAUAACUCAGAUAAUGAAGUAAAUGGAGCUCCUGUUUAUGUUGUUCGAAGUGGUGGCCUUGUAAAAACUAGAUCAAAAAACAUUCGGGUGGGUGAUAUUGUUCGAAUAGCCAAAGAUGAAAUUUUUCCUGCAGACUUGGUGCUUCUGUCCUCAGAUCGACUGGAUGGUUCCUGUCACGUUACAACUGCUAGUUUGGACGGAGAAACUAACCUGAAGACACAUGUGGCAGUUCCAGAAACAGCAUUAUUACAAACAGUUGCCAAUUUGGACACUCUAGUAGCUGUAAUAGAAUGCCAGCAACCAGAAGCAGACUUAUACAGAUUCAUGGGACGAAUGAUCAUAACCCAACAAAUGGAAGAAAUUGUAAGACCUCUGGGGCCGGAGAGUCUCCUGCUUCGUGGAGCCAGAUUAAAAAACACAAAAGAAAUUUUUGGUGUUGCGGUAUACACUGGAAUGGAAACUAAGAUGGCAUUAAAUUACAAGAGCAAAUCACAGAAACGAUCUGCAGUAGAAAAGUCAAUGAAUACAUUUUUGAUAAUUUAUCUAGUAAUUCUUAUAUCUGAAGCUGUCAUCAGCACUAUCUUGAAGUAUACAUGGCAAGCUGAAGAAAAAUGGGAUGAACCUUGGUAUAACCAAAAAACAGAACAUCAAAGAAAUAGCAGUAAGAUUCUGAGAUUUAUUUCAGACUUCCUUGCUUUUUUGGUUCUCUACAAUUUCAUCAUUCCAAUUUCAUUAUAUGUGACAGUCGAAAUGCAGAAAUUUCUUGGAUCAUUUUUUAUUGGCUGGGAUCUUGAUCUGUAUCAUGAAGAAUCAGAUCAGAAAGCUCAAGUCAAUACUUCCGAUCUGAAUGAAGAGCUUGGACAGGUAGAGUACGUGUUUACAGAUAAAACUGGUACACUGACAGAAAAUGAGAUGCAGUUUCGGGAAUGUUCAAUUAAUGGCAUGAAAUACCAAGAAAUUAAUGGUAGACUUGUACCCGAAGGACCAACACCAGACUCUUCAGAAGGAAACUUAUCUUAUCUUAGUAGUUUAUCCCAUCUUAACAACUUAUCCCAUCUUACAACCAGUUCCUCUUUCAGAACCAGUCCUGAAAAUGAAACUGAACUAAUUAAAGAACAUGAUCUCUUCUUUAAAGCAGUCAGUCUCUGUCACACUGUACAGAUUAGCAAUGUUCAAACUGACUGCACUGGUGAUGGUCCCUGGCAAUCCAACCUGGCACCAUCGCAGUUGGAGUACUAUGCAUCUUCACCAGAUGAAAAGGCUCUAGUAGAAGCUGCUGCAAGGAUUGGUAUUGUGUUUAUUGGCAAUUCUGAAGAAACUAUGGAGGUUAAAACUCUUGGAAAACUGGAACGGUACAAACUGCUUCAUAUUCUGGAAUUUGAUUCAGAUCGUAGGAGAAUGAGUGUAAUUGUUCAGGCACCUUCAGGUGAGAAGUUAUUAUUUGCUAAAGGAGCUGAGUCAUCAAUUCUCCCUAAAUGUAUAGGUGGAGAAAUAGAAAAAACCAGAAUUCAUGUAGAUGAAUUUGCUUUGAAAGGGCUAAGAACUCUGUGUAUAGCAUAUAGAAAAUUUACAUCAAAAGAGUAUGAGGAAAUAGAUAAACGCAUAUUUGAAGCCAGGACUGCCUUGCAGCAGCGGGAAGAGAAAUUGGCAGCUGUUUUCCAGUUCAUAGAGAAAGACCUGAUAUUACUUGGAGCCACAGCAGUAGAAGACAGACUACAAGAUAAAGUUCGAGAAACUAUUGAAGCAUUGAGAAUGGCUGGUAUCAAAGUAUGGGUACUUACUGGGGAUAAACAUGAAACAGCUGUUAGUGUGAGUUUAUCAUGUGGCCAUUUUCAUAGAACCAUGAACAUCCUUGAACUUAUAAACCAGAAAUCAGACAGCGAGUGUGCUGAACAAUUGAGGCAGCUUGCCAGAAGAAUUACAGAGGAUCAUGUGAUUCAGCAUGGGCUGGUAGUGGAUGGGACCAGCCUAUCUCUUGCACUCAGGGAGCAUGAAAAACUAUUUAUGGAAGUUUGCAGAAAUUGUUCAGCUGUAUUAUGCUGUCGUAUGGCUCCACUGCAGAAAGCAAAAGUAAUAAGACUAAUAAAAAUAUCACCUGAGAAACCUAUAACAUUGGCUGUUGGUGAUGGUGCUAAUGACGUAAGCAUGAUACAAGAAGCCCAUGUUGGCAUAGGAAUCAUGGGUAAAGAAGGAAGACAGGCUGCAAGAAACAGUGACUAUGCAAUAGCCAGAUUUAAGUUCCUCUCCAAAUUGCUUUUUGUUCAUGGUCAUUUUUAUUAUAUUAGAAUAGCUACCCUUGUACAGUAUUUUUUUUAUAAGAAUGUGUGCUUUAUCACACCCCAGUUUUUAUAUCAGUUCUACUGUUUGUUUUCUCAGCAAACAUUGUAUGACAGCGUGUACCUGACUUUAUACAAUAUUUGUUUUACUUCCCUACCUAUUCUGAUAUAUAGUCUUUUGGAACAGCAUGUAGACCCUCAUGUGUUACAAAAUAAGCCCACCCUUUAUCGAGACAUUAGUAAAAACCGCCUCUUAAGUAUUAAAACAUUUCUUUAUUGGACCAUCCUGGGCUUCAGUCAUGCCUUUAUUUUCUUUUUUGGAUCCUAUUUACUAAUAGGGAAAGAUACAUCUCUGCUUGGAAAUGGCCAGAUGUUUGGAAACUGGACAUUUGGCACUUUGGUCUUCACAGUCAUGGUUAUUACAGUCACAGUAAAGAUGGCUCUGGAAACUCAUUUUUGGACUUGGAUCAACCAUCUCGUUACCUGGGGAUCUAUUAUAUUUUAUUUUGUAUUUUCCUUGUUUUAUGGAGGGAUUCUCUGGCCAUUUUUGGGCUCCCAGAAUAUGUAUUUUGUGUUUAUUCAGCUCCUGUCAAGUGGUUCUGCUUGGUUUGCCAUAAUCCUCAUGGUUGUUACAUGUCUAUUUCUUGAUAUCAUAAAGAAGGUCUUUGACCGACACCUCCACCCUACAAGUACUGAAAAGGCACAGAUGUACUCCAACACAGUUGCUUUAAGUGACGAGUUCAUCGCACUGCAGCCAUUGUCGAGGGCAAGGAAUCAGCUGAGCAAACUUAGCUUACUGAAACAAAUGCAGGUAUCAAGUGCUUGGACUCCAUGUGCUGUUUCCCGGAAGGAGAAGCAGCGUGUGCAUCUGUUGGAAGAAUGCUGGAACGAGUUAUAGGAAGAUGUAGUCCAACCCACAUCAGCAGGUGUGAAAUCUCUCUAAGUAGCCUUUGCUGCAGAUGAGUAUCCUAUCUGGAACAGGAUGAACCUGCCGCUCUAGAUACCUAAUAAAUCAGCAGCUGGUUUUACCAACUGAAGCAGGAAGUCUGCUAUUUAUUAGCACUCUUUGGUGGUAGAUUUCACUUUGUGGCUUUGGGGUAAGGGCUUUUUCACUCACAAAGGAAGAGAAAGCACCUUUGAAGAGACUUCAUCUAAUGAACAAAAAAUUUUGUUUCAUAAUCUUUCUAAAAUGUGCUCAGUAGGAGUGUGUUUAUGGUACUCUUUUAUGGUUUGUAUAACUUUCUUUUUUAAAUUAUACAUAUACUAUUUCCUUUUUAUUUUUUUAAAAUUUUUUUGCUUUUUGUCUUUACAAAAUAAUCUCAACAUAACAGUGAAGUCAAAGGCUUUCCUUUUCUUACUCUGUAUGUAUAUUUUCCAGUUGGUUAUUUGAGGCUUUGAGGUAUUUAUAAACACAAAAGGCUGUAUUUCUGCUCCCCUACCUCUUCUUAUGUCUGUAAUGAAGUUUUGAAAUGAGUCAUGAUUUUUAAGUUUCUUUUGCUUGGUAUUUAUUGCCUAAUUAAAAGUGUAUGAGUUAGAACAGGCUUUUUAAAUUAUGGAGUAAAAGAAUCUUAGCAUUUUUGUCCCCUCCUAAAUCUGUUUCUUGAAUGAGAUUUAUCACCAUGCCUGCUGUUGUGCACCAUAACGAAAAAAAACACCUUUUGGUAAACACCAUUUAAAAUUCAUUUAAACUUGCAAUGGAUUUAUUUAUUCAUACAUUUCCCCAAGAGUUAUAUCACUAUUUAGAGGAUGUUAGGGGGUAGAAAGAGCUUUUUCCACACUUGGUGUUCUUUAGGUGAAUGAUACCAUAUUCUCAAAAUCAGGGCAGCAGUACACGGUAUGCAUGGAGGUACAAAUGGGCAGGGAGAGAUGUUGGUUGCCAUUGUCCCAAAUGUGCUACAUGAAUAUUAGCACUUUCUACAUGUGCCAGGGCUUGGAAAAGGUUGGAAAUUACCCCAGGAACAGGUUAUAAAGAGUGAAGAAGGCACUACUCCUAUCUACUGGAAAAAGGAUUUUUAUUAUUUGGUUAGCUUUGUGUUUUAAAAAAAUGAUGAGUAUGAUAUCAUUCAUCUGUUAUAAAAUUCAGGUAACUUUUACUGGUGAACUUGUUAGUUCUCACUUUAGCUUUAGCUUAGCCAUGCCUUUAUGAUACAAUUGAAUUUAUAAAUAGCAUUCUUAUGUUAACAUAAUGUCUGUGGUUUCAAUCCCCGUUUAUUCUGACUUGAUUAUAACGUGAUCUGAAAUAUUUCCAUAAUGCUGUGAUACCAUUUUGUAGUAAUUUCAUUCCACGUAGAAGGAUGAGCACUUAAACUCUGGGACUUUGUUAUGAUUUACAUAAUUGUAUUAUAAAAUGUGGCUCUGUCAUGUACCUAGGCCAGCAAAUUUCCCAAAGAGCUUGAUUUAUAAUACUAUUUUACCUAAUAACAUAGCUUCAUUGCACAGAAUCAAGAUAGGAGUUAGACUAAGAUACAAUAGAACCUCUACAGAAUUUUUUCAACUUCUCCUUCAAUGGAAAUUUCUCUUUAAUGACAAUAUACGUUUUUGUUAAUGAUUUUUUUAAAACUAGAAUUAAUUUUAAAUGAGCCCCAGAUUUUUUCUGCUAUAUACAUAUAUCCAUUUUCUUGAUAUCGAUUAUGGUAAUAUGCCCCCAUUAUUCUUUACAUAGCCAUUUUGAUGCAGCAUUACCUCUUUUGAACCUGCCCCAGGAGUUAUUGAAUUUACUUUUACAUGUUCUCUUGAAGGUAGCUAUUAUCAUCUAUACUUCUUUUCACUUAAAAUUGCGCCAUAUUGUUUUUUUCUGAAUUUUUUUAUUCUCCUAAUAAAAUGUUUAACUUAGUAAUUAAUAUCAUAUUAGACUAUAAAUGCCCUUCCAGGUUUCUCCAACAUCACAGGUUAUAUUAUUGGUUACUAUUAUUUUCUUACCCUUUUUCUCAUGUGAAUAAUCUAGAAGGUCUUUUCAGACCUGUUCAUUCUUUUCUAGGGGAUAAAGUCAUAUAAUAACACCAAGCUACCUGGUGCUUUUCAAGGGCUAUGUGAAAAUUGCCAUAGAUGCAUCAAUAUUGUAUUUAAACUUGCAAAGUCAUUUUGAUACAUAGAGUUCUCUUUUUGUUUACAUAUAAUUGUAUUUGUGAAAUGUGUUGGGCAUUUCCAUUGUGACUUUAGAGUAGCAUCUAUUCUAUGUUUCUAUUUCAUGUCUAAUUUAAGAGGUGGGGCAAGUCUGAGACUGCCAUUCCAAGAUGUAGAAGCCCUUAGCUGUGUGUUCCAUUGACAUAGUAAAGUCAAGAGUAAUGGGCAUCACUUGAGAAAUGCCACCAGUGUUUUUAUGUGACAGAUUUCUUUGGUGAUUACAUUUGUACCAUCCAGGCACAAAAAUUUGACUUACAUUUUAUUAAUUGAUGUUGUCAAUGAAGUAUCCCAUAUUGCAAGCUCAGUUUCAAAGAGAGCAUCAUGGUGCUAUAUAAAGAAUAUGCCAUGUUGCACCCUAAAGAGCUGGAUUUUAGCAAUAAAAGAUUUUCUGUUCGUGUAUUACUAACAGUUAAGCUACUGUAUCCUCAUCAAAACUAUCUUCUAAAUAGAAAGUAAUAUGUAGUUCAAGUGUUUAAUGUUCUGUCAAAAAUUAUAUUUAACAUAUGAAUGCACAUGUGUGCUUUGAAAAAAAAUUUAAAAUGAAGGAGACUUUACCUAAUAAGAUUAUUCUGUGUAAGCAAUGUGGAAAGAAGAAAAACUAAUAUAAAGUAUUGGCAGUUUGGAAUUGGACAUCUGACUCCGGAUAAUUGGAGUACUGAUAGCUGUUAUAGUUAAAAGUUAUAGUUAAAAGCAUACUUGUCCCCUGUAAAUACUUACUCUUUAAGAAAUUUUCAUCUUCUCAUUUUAUUCAUUUAUUCUGCAAAUACUGGGUGCCCAAUAUAUGUCAGACACAGUUCUAGAUGCUAGGGAGACAGUAGUGAACAAGUCCUUCCCUAACCUAAGGUAGAUACUGUUCCAGCUUUUCUAGAAACUAGUCGAAUUAAAGUUGAGCUACAUACAAACUUAGCAUCUCUGGGAAAGAGAAAAUAUUUGACAAAGGUGAAUUGGGGCCUUUUUUAACGCUCAUCUCUUCCUGUAACAUCUCUGUUUAGGGAAGGUGGGAACCCUGGAAAAAGUUACAUAAAAUGUAUUUAUUGUUAAAUGUGUUUAGUCUCAUAAGAAAAGCAGUCUUUCACUUGGUAAUCCUAAUACUGUCCUUGAACUAGGUUAGUCUAUUUUAAGCAUGGCAGGCUACUUUUGGUCUUGAGUUAUUUUAGCUUAAAUUAACUCAAGCUAAUUUAAGUUUACAGCUGCACAUAAAGUAUUAUGUAAUGACUUGCUUUAGGGCCUUAUCAUUCAAACACCAGUUAACUUUUCCAGACCAGUAGAGGAUCGUUUGUCCUUAUUAAGUGAAAACGCUAGUGACCUACAGGUGUCUUUGAUGCCUUUUGAAUACAUCAUUCGCUACAUUCAAGCUAAUUAUGCGGAAGUCUUUAGAAUAGGAUUUAUAGCUGAAAUGAAAUGAUCAAUAAUAGGAACAUACUACUGUUUCAUUCCAAAGCCUUUGGUAAGUGGGAUUUGGGUUUGUUUUUGUAAACUGAACUUUUCAGUAAAACAAUGUGCAUAACUCUUAAUAACAUACUUCUUAUUGAAUUGUUAACACUUUAAAAGCAGCUCAUGCUUUACUACAUAUAGAAACUGUUUUAAUGCUAAUGAAUGUUUGAAUUUUGGCUAAUAUUUUUAUAUGAUGACUAGAGCAUUAUUUUUCCCAAGUUUUUAUAUAAUAUAAAUAGAAAGUUUGGGCAUUCGAUACUAGUAUGAAGAACCUCUCUUUAGUAUUUAAAUGAAUCAAUCAGUGAUUGCAUUUGGGUCCUAAGUUUUAGAGUAAAUUUUUUUCUCAAUUAAAACAUAGGUCCUGGUGAGCCAAACUUUUCUCUUAUUGUUACUUUAGAUCAUGGAGUGCAUCGGAUCCUUUCUAUACCAACGACAGGAGCAUCUUGACUCUCUCCACAAUGGACUCAUCUACUUGUUAAAGGGGCAGUAGUACUUUGUGGGAGCCAGUUCACCUCCUUUCCUAAAAUUCAGUGUGAUCACCCUGUUAAUGGCCACACUAGCUCUGAAAUUAAUUUCCAAAAUCUUUGUAGUAGUUCAUACCCACUCAGAGUUAUAAUGGCAAACAAACAGAAAGCAUUAGUACAAGCCCCUCCCAACACCCUUAAUUUGAAUCUGAACAUGUUAAAAUUUGAGAAUAAAGAGACAUUUUUCAUCUCUUUGUCUGGUUUGUCCCUUGUGCUUAUGGGACUCCUAAUGGCAUUUCAGUCUGUUGCUGAGGCCAUUAUAUUUUAAUAUAAAUGUAGAAAAAAGAGAGAAAUCUUAGUAAAGAGUAUUUUUUAGUAUUAGCUUGAUUAUUGACUCUUCUAUUUAAAUCUGCUUCUGUAAAUUAUGCUGAAAGUUUGCCUUGAGAACUCUAUUUUUUUAUUAGAGUUAUAUUUAAAGCUUUUCAUGGGAAAAGUUAAUGUGAAUACUGAGGAAUUUUGGUCCCUCAGUGACCUGUGUUGUUAAUUCAUUAAUGCAUUCUGAGUUCACAGAGCAAAUUAGGAGAAUCAUUUCCAACCAUUAUUUACUGCAGUAUGGGGAGUAAAUUUAUACCAAUUCCUCUAACUGUACUGUAACACAGCCUGUAAAGUUAGCCAUAUAAAUGCAAGGGUAUAUCAUAUAUACAAAUCAGGAAUCAGGUCCGUUCACCGAACUUCAAAUUGAUGUUUACUAAUAUUUUUGUGACAGAGUAUAAAGACCCUAUAGUGGGUAAAUUAGAUACUAUUAGCAUAUUAUUAAUUUAAUGUCUUUAUCAUUGGAUCUUUUGCAUGCUUUAAUCUGGUUAACAUAUUUAAAUUUGCUUUUUUUCUCUUUACCUGAAGGCUCUGUGUAUAGUAUUUCAUGACAUCGUUGUACAGUUUAACUAUAUCAAUAAAAAGUUUGGACAGUAUUUAAAUAUUGCAAAUAUGUUUAAUUAUACAAAUCAGAAUAGUAUGGGUAAUUAAAUGAAUACAAAAAGAAGAGCCUCUUUCUGCAGCCGACUUAGACAUGCUCUUCCCUUUCUAUAAGCUAGAUUUUAGAAUAAAGGGUUUCAGUUAAUAAUCUUAUUUUCAGGUUAUGUCAUCUAACUUAUAGCAAACUACCACAAUACAGUGAGUUCUGCCAGUGUCCCAGUACAAGGCAUAUUUCAGGUGUGGCUGUGGAAUGUAAAAAUGCUCAACUUGUAUCAGGUAAUGUUAGCAAUAAAUUAAAUGCUAAGAAUGAUUAAUCGGGUACAUGUUACUGUAAUUAACUCAUUGCACUUCAAAACCUAACUUCCAUCCUGAAUUUAUCAAGUAGUUCAGUAUUGUCAUUUGUUUUUGUUUUAUUGAAAAGUAAUGUUGUCUUAAGAUUUAGAAGUGAUUAUUAGCUUGAGAACUAUUACCCAGCUCUAAGCAAAUAAUGAUUGUAUACAUAUUAAGAUAAUGGUUAAAUGCGGUUUUACCAAGUUUUCCCUUGAAAAUGUAAUUCCUUUAUGGAGAUUUAUUGUGCAGCCCUAAGCUUCCUUCCCAUUUCAUGAAUAUAAGGCUUCUAGAAUUGGACUGGCAGGGGAAAGAAUGGUAGAGACAGAAAUUAAGACUUUAUCCUUGUUUGCUUGUAAACUAUUAUUUUCUUGCUAAUGUAACAUUUGUCUGUUCCAGUGAUGUAAGGAUAUUAAGUUAUUAAGCUAAAUAUUAAUUUUCAAAAAUAGUCCUUCUUUAACUUAGAUAUUUCAUAGCUGGAUUUAGGAAGAUCUGUUAUUCUGGAAGUACUAAAAAGAAUAAUACAACGUACAAUGUCUGCAUUCACUAAUUCAUGUUCCAGAAGAGGAAAUAAUGAAGAUAUACUCAGUAGAGUACUAGGUGGGAGGAUAUGGAAAUUUGCUCAUAAAAUCUCUUAUAAAACGUGCAUAUAACAAAAUGACACCCAGUAGGCCUGCAUUACAUUUACAUGACCGUGUUUAUUUGCCAUCAAAUAAACUGAGUACUGACACCAGACAAAGACUCCAAAGUCAUAAAAUAGCCUAUGACCAACUGCAGCAAGACAGGAGGUCAGCUCGCCUAUAAUGGUGCUUAAAGUGUGAUUGAUGUAAUUUUCUGUACUCACCAUUUGAAGUUAGUUAAGGAGAACUUUAUUUUUUUAAAAAAAGUAAAUGGCAACCACUAGUGUGCUCAUCCUGAACUGUUACUCCAAAUCCACUCCGUUUUUAAAGCAAAAUUAUCUUGUGAUUUUAAGAAAAGAGUUUUCUAUUUAUUUAAGAAAGUAACAAUGCAGUCUGCAAGCUUUCAGUAGUUUUCUAGUGCUAUAUUCAUCCUGUAAAACUCUUACUACGUAACCAGUAAUCACAAGGAAAGUGUCCCCUUUGCAUAUUUCUUUAAAAUUCUUUCUUUGGAAAGUAUGAUGUUGAUAAUUAACUUACCCUUAUCUGCCAAAACCAGAGCAAAAUGCUAAAUACGUUAUUGCUAAUCAGUGGUCUCAAAUCGAUUUGCCUCCCUUUGCCUCGUCUGAGGGCUGUAAGCCUGAAGAUAGUGGCAAGCACCAAGUCAGUUUCCAAAAUUGCCCCUCAGCUGCUUUAAGUGACUCAGCACCCUGCCUCAGCUUCAGCAGGCGUAGGCUCACCCUGGGCGGAGCAAAGUAUGGGCCAGGGAGAACUACAGCUACGAAGACCUGCUGUCGAGUUGAGAAAAGGGGAGAAUUUAUGGUCUGAAUUUUCUAACUGUCCUCUUUCUUGGGUCUAAAGCUCAUAAUACACAAAGGCUUCCAGACCUGAGCCACACCCAGGCCCUAUCCUGAACAGGAGACUAAACAGAGGCAAAUCAACCCUAGGAAAUACUUGCAUUCUGCCCUACGGUUAGUACCAGGACUGAGGUCAUUUCUACUGGAAAAGAUUGUGAGAUUGAACUUAUCUGAUCGCUUGAGACUCCUAAUAGGCAGGAGUCAAGGCCACUAGAAAAUUGACAGUUAAGAGCCAAAAGUUUUUAAAAUAUGCUACUCUGAAAAAUCUCGUGAAGGCUGUAGGAAAAGGGAGAAUCUUCCAUGUUGGUGUUUUUCCUGUAAAGAUCAGUUUGGGGUAUGAUAUAAGCAGGUAUUAAUAAAAAUAACACACCAAAGAGUUACGUAAAACAUGUUUUAUUAAUUUUGGUCCCCACGUACAGACAUUUUAUUUCUAUUUUGAAAUGAGUUAUCUAUUUUCAUAAAAGUAAAACACUAUUAAAGUGCUGUUUUAUGUGAAAUAACUUGAAUGUUGUUCCUAUAAAAAAUAGAUCAUAACUCAUGAUAUGUUUGUAAUCAUGGUAAUUUAGAUUUUUAUGAGGAAUGAGUAUCUGGAAAUAUUGUAGCAAUACUUGGUUUAAAAUUUUGGACCUGAGACACUGUGGCUGUCUAAUGUAAUCCUUUAAAAAUUCUCUGCAUUGUCAGUAAAUGUAGUAUAUUAUUGUACAGCUACUCAUAAUUUUUUAAAGUUUAUGAAGUUAUAUUUAUCAAAUAAAAACUUUCCUAUAUAA